AUGGUGCACGCUCCCUGGCCUCUCGGACACCCCAGAGAGGGGCGAGCCGAGGGACCCCAGUGCGCAGCUUGGACAGCGGCGGCGCCAGCACUUAGGGAGUGCGACAAGGGGUGCAGGCGGGCGGGCAGGGGCUGCCCCCGACUCCAGGUGAGCUGGCGGGAAGCGGGACUCGGUCCAGCCGCGCGCCGCCGGUCCCGGAGUUGUGCCGAGUGCGGGAAAGGCGCUGAUCCCCACCGCGCUCUUUCUGAAGAGUGGAAGCCGAGAAGCGGCACCCGGUGCGCCUCGCCGCUCCAGUCCGGCGGUGCUGCGGGCACAAGGGCUCCAGCCGCGGGCCCCCAGGACGCUCUCUGGGACGCCUUCGAGGGCGGGCGGCGGCGCUGGGGGCUUUCCUUCCUCACAUUCCCGCCGGGGUGGCGAGGAGCGGGUGGAGACGCUGGGGGUUGUGUCCCGGCUGUGUUCGCGCGCCGCAGCGGAAGCCUGCUCUCAGUCCCUUGCUCUUGUCUUCUCAGAACCUCUCCGGAUCCAGCAGCAAGAUCCCAAAGCAAGGAAAGAAAGAAAAAGCGAGGGGGCGGGGGCGCUGCAGAAUCCAGCGUCCUCCCAAGUCCUCCUGUGGGAAGACAGCAGCGCUGCUACUGGUGGAGAGGGGCUGCGAGAGGGAGGCGCGGAGGGACCCCUUGGCUCUCCGCCGGGUCUGGCGCUAACGGCCCCGCGAGCAAGCUCGGGAGGCGGCCGCUGCACCGCGGGUGGAGGAGCGGGAGGAGCGUCCCCGCGGGGCUGCACGACCUCCUGGAGGGGGUGAUGCUCGUUCACCUCUCUUCAGCUUUGUGAAAUACCGCAAGGUCUUUGGAGAUGAGCCAGGAAAAUCCAUUCACGUGCGGAAAUUUGCCGGGCUACGCGCGUUGCUGCUGAUGCCUAGGGUUCGGAGUGAAAGGAGGGGAGAAAGCGAAGGGAUUCCUCCUCCUGCUCCCAGCUGCUGCGUUGAUGUGCUGGGGUGUAUCGAACAGCGGCAACAAAAAGCGCUUUCACUGCAAGGCAGACAUCAAUAGGAGCCCACGGAGAUGGAGGGGUGCUGCACAUAGGUGUUUGGCAUGUGAGACAGUCCAUAAGAAAGAAUCAAUUCGGAGGGCUGCUGCCUGACUGCAGUUUGAUCAUGGCGGGUGGGGGCGGGUGGAAUUCCUAAAACUCCAGCCGAGCAUGUUUAACUUAUUUUUCUUCAGUAAUUUGGAGUCACGGUCCCUCCCAGUUCUUCGCUGUCACCGGAAUUACUCCGUUUGGCUCUCCCAAGGCUCCUGUCAAGAAGGCCUAAGAAGUAGAAUGGCCUUCAUUUUCAGGAUAAGGAAGCUGAGGUUCAGGGUUUAAAAUGAUUUCUCUGAGGUCAGUGGCAAGUGGCAUAUGGAAAUAGAACGUGGGUCUCCUGCGUGUGUCUAUAGCUAGUGGCGUCCUCACUGCAUGGCCUGCAGAAAUCCCACCCAACACAGCCGGGCCGGUUUGGCCUUCCUACAUAUAAAGAUGGUGCGAUUGAAAUCAAACAGAGUGUACCAUGACGAAUAGAACCAUGAUAGGGUCUGGAAGACCCCAAGUAAACAGUUGGCACUUAGUUUAGACACUUUUUGCUGUCUAGCUGGCCUACUAGCUGAGUGCCUGACCUUCUGUAACUUACCAGGAAGAAGGGCUGUGCUUCCCAGGCAGGUCCCAGGGAAGUGCUUGCAAAGCAGAAGGAAAGCUCCAGACUGUUCUGCCCUAGCCUAUGAUAAAUAAUUUCUGAGCCCAUCUUGUCUGGGUUGUCUGCCUUUCUCGGGCUUGUUCACAAAUAAAUCUCUCUCCGACUGUGCGUUCUGGUGCAACUGAGAGCUCUGGGGCGAAUGGCUCUCCAGCUUUUCUGACAGCUCCUCUUCUCCCAGUCCUACCCCUGAACCCCCCACCUGUUAAAAGGCAUUGGCUCAUCUGUGAAUUUCCCUAACUUCCUCUUCAGAUUCUGAAACGUGAGAGUGAAAUUUCAGACUAACACCCAGCCACCCCAACAACUCCCUAGAGCUAGCCUUCUGUCCCAACUUCCCUGUGCCAUCCACAACUCAUACAUUAAACUCUGCAGAUUAGUGCAUCCUAAACAUAGAAAACAACGAAGCCAUUAGACCUCUUCCCAUUCUCUCGAAUAGCCUAAUGUGCCUCUGAAUAUAACACAACCUUGGAAAUGUAUUCUGCACCAGCAUCAUGCCAGGAUGGGGAAGAGGAAAGAAGUCAAGGCCUCCCUUUAAGAAAAGGUUUUUCUUAGGAAGCAGUGCACCCCUCUCCCCUAAGUUACUGAAGUCUGGUUCAUCCUGUUGGAAAUUUUAAAUUUGGUUAAAAUGCCUUGUGUUUGCUGGAAUAAAAUUCAUGUUGUUACUGAA